GUAGCCGGCGGCCGUGGUUCCGGAGCGGGAGUCGGAGGUGAGUGUGCGAACUGGACCGGGGCCCCAGAGACUUCGGACUCGCUCUCGGGGAGAACGGUGACCGAGGGAUGGUGCCAUGAGUGAAACAAGCUGCUCAGCAGGCACUUACUAAACACCGACUACGUGCCAUGCCCAGUGUUAAGGUCUGGGGAUUGAAAGAAGAGUAGGACAGAGUCCAUCUUGGAGGCACUUUCUGUCCCAUUCCCUUCCCAGAUGCUGGAGCCACAGCUGCUUUUAGGAUUCUUGUGUCUUUCUCCGUCUCCCAAGGGGUAGGUAAGAGUCUCCCUCUGCCCUGGCUUUCAUCUCUGAGACCCCUAGUUGUAGAGGUGGUGACUUAGGGUGAAGAUUUCCAUCAGGAUUACUUGGUAAGCUUAUUAGAAAGACAGGUUCCAGUGUUGCACAUGUGUCCAGCCUCAAACGGUGUGGUCCCUAGACUUGAGGCCAUGCCCUUCUACUUUGGAUUCGGGGUGAGGUGGAGAGGGGGAUGUUUGAAAUGAGAUUAGUGAGUAAAUAAGUAGAAUAUAAGGCAGAGUAAGAUAUAUCUCCAGCGGCAAAGAGAACAACACACACUUGGAGAAGAAAUAAGCAUAUAAGCAUGUACUGGAUUGCUGGGGCCCCAGUGGCUCGUACUAGAGCCUGAGAGGGAGGGCACUGAAGGGACAGUGUCUUGAUGUCAUAGUUAGAUCUUGGACUUUGAAGGCAAACUAGUGGGUUUGACUCUUGGCCGCAUGGUUAAUUGAAGGGGUGGGUUGCCCCUCCACACCUGUGGGUGUUUCUCGUUAGGUGGAACGAGAGACUUGGAAAAGAAAAAGACACAGAGACAAAGUAUAGAGAAAGAAAUAAGGGGGCCCAGGGGACCAGCGUUCAGCGUACGGAGGAUCCAUCCUGGCCUCUGAGUUCCCUUAGUAUUUAUUGAUCAUUCUUGGGUGUUUCUCAGAGAGGGGGAUGUGGCAGGGUCACAGGAUAAUAGUGGAGAGAAGGUCAGCAGAUAAACACGUGAACAAAGGUUUCUGCAUCAUAGACAAGGUAAAGAAUUAAGUGCUGUGCUUUAGAUAUGCAUACCCAUAAACAUCUCAAUGCCUUACAGAGCAGCAUUGUUGCCCGCAUGUCCCACCUCCAGCCCUAAGGCGGUUUUCCCCUAUCUCAGUAGAUGGAACAUACAAUCGGGUUUUAUACCGAGACAUUCCAUUGCCCAGGGACGGGCAGGAGACAGAUGCCUUCCUCUUGUCUCAACUGCAAGAGGCAUGCCUUCCUCUUAUACUAAUGCUCCUCAGCACAGACCCUUUACGGGUGUCGGGCUGGGGGACAGUCAGGUCUUUCCCUUCCCACGAGGCCAUAUUUCAGACUAUCACAUGGGGAGAAACCUUGGACAAUACCUGGCUUUCCUAGGCAGAGGUCCCUGCGGUCUUCCGGCCUUCCGCAAUGUUUGUGUCCCUGGGUAGUUGAGAUUAGGGAGUGGUGAUGACUCUUAACGAGCAUGCUGCCUUCAAGCAUCUGUUUAACAAAGCACAUCUUGCACAGCCCUUAAUCCAUUUAACCGUGAGUGGACACAGCACAUGUUUCAGAGAGCACGGGGUUGGGGGUAAGGUUAUAGAUUAACAGCAUCUCAAGCUGAAGAAUUUCUCUUAGUACAGAACAAAAUGGAGUCUCCUAUGUCUACUUCUUUCUACACAGACACAGUAACAAUCUGAUCUCUCUUUCUUUUCCCCACAUUAGGGAGGGCACUGAAGGGACAGUGUCUUGAUGUCAUAGUUAGAUCUUGGACUUUGAAGGCAAACUAGUGGGUUUGACUCUUGGCCACAUGGUUAAUCACCUGUGACCUUGGGCAAGUCACCAGAAUCCUCUCUGUGUCAGUUUCCUCAUCUGCAAAAUGGAAUAAUGCCUUAAACAAGGAGGACCUUGUUUCUAUCUAUGAAGCAUGGAGAACAGUGCCUGGAAGAUAGGAUGGUGCCUUGAGUGAAUGACCCCCUUGGAGAACAUUCUUCCGCAUCCCUCGCCUCAAGCCAGCCUCAGACAGAAAACUGAAGAUUCAGCAGAUCCAGUGCUUCCUGCUCCUCUUCUGCCCAGGAACACGCUUGCCUUCCCCAAGGCUUCCAGAAGCUCUGAGGCAGGAGGCACCAAGUUCUACCUCAUGUUUGGAGGAUCUUGCUAGCUAUGGCCCUCGUACUCGGCUCCCUGUUGCUGCUGGGGCUGUGCGGGAACUCCUUUUCAGGAGGGCAGCCUUCAUCCACAGAUGCUCCUAAGGCUUGGAAUUAUGAAUUGCCUGCAACAAAUUAUGAGACCCAAGACUCCCAUAAAGCUGGACCCAUUGGCAUUCUCUUUGAACUAGUGCAUAUCUUUCUCUAUGUGGUACAGCCGCGUGAUUUCCCAGAAGAUACUUUGAGAAAAUUCUUACAGAAGGCAUAUGAAUCCAAAAUUGAUUAUGACAAGAUUGUCUACUAUGAAGCAGGGAUUAUUCUAUGCUGUGUCCUGGGGCUGCUGUUUAUUAUUCUGAUGCCUCUGGUGGGGUAUUUCUUUUGUAUGUGUCGUUGCUGUAACAAAUGUGGUGGAGAAAUGCACCAGCGACAGAAGGAAAAUGGGCCCUUCCUGAGGAAAUGCUUUGCAAUCUCCCUGUUGGUGAUUUGUAUAAUAAUAAGCAUUGGCAUCUUCUAUGGUUUUGUGGCAAAUCACCAGGUAAGAACCCGGAUCAAAAGGAGUCGGAAACUGGCAGAUAGCAAUUUCAAGGACUUGCGAACUCUCUUGAAUGAAACUCCAGAGCAAAUCAAAUAUAUAUUGGCCCAGUACAACACUACCAAGGACAAGGCGUUCACAGAUCUGAACAGUAUCAAUUCAGUGCUAGGAGGCGGAAUUCUUGACCGACUGAGACCCAACAUCAUCCCUGUUCUUGAUGAGAUUAAGUCCAUGGCAACAGCGAUCAAGGAGACCAAAGAGGCGUUGGAGAACAUGAACAGCACCUUGAAGAGCUUGCACCAACAAAGUACACAGCUUAGCAGCAGUCUGACCAGCGUGAAAACUAGCCUGCGGUCAUCUCUCAAUGACCCUCUGUGCUUGGUGCAUCCAUCAAGUGAAACCUGCAACAGCAUCAGAUUGUCUCUAAGCCAGCUGAAUAGCAACCCUGAACUGAGGCAGCUUCCACCCGUGGAUGCAGAACUUGACAACGUUAAUAACGUUCUUAGGACAGAUUUGGAUGGCCUGGUCCAACAGGGCUAUCAAUCCCUUAAUGAUAUACCUGACAGAGUACAACGCCAAACCACGACUGUCGUAGCAGGUAUCAAAAGGGUCUUGAAUUCCAUUGGUUCAGAUAUCGACAAUGUAACUCAGCGUCUUCCUAUUCAGGAUAUACUCUCAGCAUUCUCUGUUUAUGUUAAUAACACUGAAAGUUACAUCCACAGAAAUUUACCUACAUUGGAAGAGUAUGAUUCAUACUGGUGGCUGGGUGGCCUGGUCAUCUGCUCUCUGCUGACCCUCAUCGUGAUUUUUUACUACCUGGGCUUACUGUGUGGCGUGUGCGGCUAUGACAGGCAUGCCACCCCGACCACCCGAGGCUGUGUCUCCAACACCGGAGGCGUCUUCCUCAUGGUUGGAGUUGGAUUAAGUUUCCUCUUUUGCUGGAUAUUGAUGAUCAUUGUGGUUCUUACCUUUGUCUUUGGUGCAAAUGUGGAAAAACUGAUCUGUGAACCUUACACGAGCAAGGAAUUAUUCCGGGUUUUGGAUACACCCUACUUACUAAAUGAAGACUGGGAAUACUAUCUCUCUGGGAAGCUAUUUAAUAAAUCAAAAAUGAAGCUCACUUUUGAACAAGUUUACAGUGACUGCAAAAAAAAUAGAGGCACUUACGGCACUCUUCACCUGCAGAACAGCUUCAAUAUCAGUGAACAUCUCAACAUUAAUGAGCAUACUGGAAGCAUAAGCAGUGAAUUGGAAAGUCUGAAGGUAAAUCUUAAUAUCUUUCUGUUGGGUGCAGCAGGAAGAAAAAACCUUCAGGAUUUUGCUGCUUGUGGAAUAGACAGAAUGAAUUAUGACAGCUACUUGGCUCAGACUGGUAAAUCCCCCGCAGGAGUGAAUCUUUUAUCAUUUGCAUAUGAUCUAGAAGCAAAAGCAAACAGUUUGCCCCCAGGAAAUUUGAGGAACUCCCUGAAAAGAGAUGCACAAACUAUUAAAACAAUUCACCAGCAACGAGUCCUUCCUAUAGAACAAUCACUGAGCACUCUAUACCAAAGCGUCAAGAUACUUCAACGCACAGGGAAUGGAUUGUUGGAGAGAGUAACUAGGAUUCUAGCUUCUCUGGAUUUUGCUCAGAACUUCAUCACAAACAAUACUUCCUCUGUUAUUAUUGAGGAAACUAAGAAGUAUGGGAGAACAAUAAUAGGAUAUUUUGAACAUUAUCUGCAGUGGAUCGAGUUCUCUAUCAGUGAGAAAGUGGCAUCGUGCAAACCUGUGGCCACCGCUCUAGAUACUGCUGUUGAUGUCUUUCUGUGUAGCUACAUUAUCGACCCCUUGAAUUUGUUUUGGUUUGGCAUAGGAAAAGCUACUGUAUUUUUACUUCCGGCUCUAAUUUUUGCGGUAAAACUGGCUAAGUACUAUCGUCGAAUGGAUUCGGAGGACGUGUACGAUGAUGUUGAAACUAUACCCAUGAAAAAUAUGGAAAAUGGUAAUAAUGGUUAUCAUAAAGAUCAUGUAUAUGGUAUUCACAAUCCUGUUAUGACAAGCCCAUCACAACAUUGAUAGCUGAUGUUGAAACUGCUUGAGCAUCAGGAUACUCAAAGUGGAAAGGAUCACAGAUUUUUGGUAGUUUCUGGGUCUACAAGGACUUUCCAAAUCCAGGAGCAACGCCAGUGGCAACGUAGUGACUCAGGCGGGCACCAAGGCAACGGCACCAUUGGUCUCUGGGUAGUGCUUUAAGAAUGAACACAAUCACGUUAUAGUCCAUGGUCCAUCACUAUUCAAGGAUGACUCCCUCCCUUCCUGUCUAUUUUUGUUUUUUACUUUUUUACACUGAGUUUCUAUUUAGACACUACAACAUAUGGGGUGUUUGUUCCCAUUGGAUGCAUUUCUAUCAAAACUCUAUCAAAUGUGAUGGCUAGAUUCUAACAUAUUGCCAUGUGUGGAGUGUGCUGAACACACACCAGUUUACAGGAAAGAUGCAUUUUGUGUACAGUAAACGGUGUAUAUACCUUUUGUUACCACAGAGUUUUUUAAACAAAUGAGUAUUAUAGGACUUUCUUCUAAAUGAGCUAAAUAAGUCACCAUUGACUUCUUGGUGCUGUUGAAAAUAAUCCAUUUUCACUAAAAGUGUGUGAAACCUACAGCAUAUUCUUCACGCAGAGAUUUUCAUCUAUUAUACUUUAUCAAAGAUUGGCCAUGUUCCACUUGGAAAUGGCAUGCAAAAGCAAUCAUAGAGAAACCUGCGUAACUCCAUCUGACAAAUUCAAAAGAGAGAGAGAGAUCUUGAGAGAGAAAUGCUGUUCGUUCAAAAGUGGAGUUGUUUUAACAGAUGCCAAUUACGGUGUACAGUUUAACAGAGUUUUCUGUUGCAUUACGAUAAACAUUAAUUGGAGUGCAGCUAACAUGAGUAUCAUCAGACUAGUAUCAAGUGUUCUAAAAUGAAAUAUGAGAAGAUCCUGUCACAAUUCUUAGAUCUGGUGUCCAGCAUGGAUGAAACCUUUGAGUUUGGUCCCUAAAUUUGCAUGAAAGCACAAGGUAAAUAUUCAUUUGCUUCAGGAGUUUCAUGUUGGAUCUGUCAUUAUCAAAAGUGAUCAGCAAUGAAGAACUGGUCGGACAAAAUUUAACGUUGAUGUAAUGAAAUUCCAGAUGUAGGCAUUCCCCCCAGGUCUUUUCAUGUGCAGAUUGCAGUUCUGAUUCAUUUGAAUAAAAAGGAACUUGGAAAACA